CUAACUUACGCCUCGGGGAUCAGAGAGAAGCGAGGUUCUCGUUCUGAGGGACAGGCUUGAGAUCGGCUGAAGAGAGCGGGCCCAGGCUCUGUGAGGAGGCAAGCAUCAUGCACUAUCCUGUUGGGAGCAUCCUCACCUCCAAGACACUGUUUGGGCCUGAGGAGAAGGAGUCUGCAGUGACCCUGUCGUGGUAUUUUCCACAAGAAUUCUGAAAUGAAGCAAGCACAGGUUCUCAGGGGACAGGCUGACCAGGAUCACCAGGAAGCUCCAGAGGAUCCCCAGGAGGCCCUAGAGGAGCACCAAAGGAGAAGAUCUGCCAGUGGGUCUCCAUUGCCCAGCUCCUGCCCACACUCCUGCCUGUUGCGGUGACCAGAGUCGUCAUGUCUCUUGAGCAGAAGAGUCAGCACUGCAAGCCUGAGGAAGGCCUUGACACCCAAGAAGAGGCCCUGGGCCUGGUGGGUGUGCAGGCUGCCACUACUGAGGAGCAGGAGGCUGUGUCCUCCUCCUCUCCUCUGGUCCCAGGCACCCUGGGGGAGGUGCCUGCUGCUGGGUCACCAGGUCCUCUCAAGAGUCCUCAGGGAGCCUCCGCCAUCCCCACUGCCAUCGAUUUCACUCUAUGGAGGCAAUCCAUUAAGGGCUCCAGCAACCAAGAAGAGGAGGGGCCAAGCACCUCCCCUGACCCAGAGUCUGUGUUCCGAGCAGCACUCAGUAAGAAGGUGGCUGACUUGAUUCAUUUUCUGCUCCUCAAGUAUUAAGUCAAGGAGCCGGUCACAAAGGCAGAAAUGCUGGAGAGAGUCAUCAAAAAUUACAAGCGCUGCUUUCCUGUGAUCUUCGGCAAAGCCUCCGAGUCCUUGCAGCUGGUCUUUGGCAUUGACGUGAAGGAAGCGGACCCCACCAGCAACACCUACACCCUUGUCACCUGCCUGGGACUCCUAUGAUGGCCUGGUGGUUGAUAAUAAUCAGAUCAUGCCCAAGACGGGCCUCCUGAUAAUCGUCUUGGGCAUGAUUGCAAUGGAGGGCAAAUGCGUCCCUGAGGAGAAAAUCUGGGAGGAGCUGAGUGUGAUGAAGGUGUAUGUUGGGAGGGAGCACAGUGUCUGUGGGGAGCCCAGGAAGCUGCUCACCCAAGAUUUGGUGCAGGAAAACUACCUGGAGUACCGGCAGGUGCCCAGCAGUGAUCCCAUAUGCUAUGAGUUACUGUGGGGUCCAAGGGCACUCGCUGCUUGAAAGUACUGGAGCACGUGGUCAGGGUCAAUGCAAGAGUUCUCAUUUCCUACCCAUCCCUGCAUGAAGCAGCUUUGAGAGAGGAGGAAGAGGGAGUCUGAGCAUGAGCUGCAGCCAGGGCCACUGCGAGGGGGGCUGGGCCAGUGCACCUUCCAGGGCUCCGUCCACUAGUUUCCCCUGCCUUAAUGUGACAUGAGGCCCAUUCUUCUCUCUUUGAAGAGAGCAGUCAACAUUCUUAGUAGUGGGUUUCUGUUCUAUUGGAUGACUUUGAGAUUUGUCUUUGUUUCCUUUUGGAAUUGUUCAAAUGUUCCUUUUAAUGGGUGGUUGAAUGAACUUCAGCAUUCAAAUUUAUGAAUGACAGUAGUCACACAUAGUGCUGUUUAUAUAGUUUAGGAGUAAGAGUCUUGUUUUUUAUUCAGAUUGGGAAAUCCAUUCCAUUUUGUGAAUUGGGACAUAGUUACAGCAGUGGAAUAAGUAUUCAUUUAGAAAUGUGAAUGAGCAGUAAAACUGAUGACAUAAAGAAAUUAAAAGAUAUUUAAUUCUUGCCUUAUACUCAGUCUACUCGGUAAAAUUUUUUUUAAAAAAUGUGCAUACCUGGAUUUCCUUGGCUUCUUUGAGAAUGUAAGACAAAUUAAAUCUGAAUAAAUCAUU